ACAUAAAAAAGCAUAAUAAGCAUGUCACAGUGUAAAAUUUGAUAAAGAGAAAUGACAAUGAUAUUGAAUUCUCAAAGAAGCCUCAUUAGGCAUAUAUAUCCUUUAUGUAUGUUACUGGCCAUACUUGGGUUUUAUUUUAUAUUAAUAAUUUGAAUUUAUUUAGCCAUUUUUGAUGUCUCUCUCUAUCCUAUCCAUAUUGCCAAUAGCUUAUCAAACUCUUUUCCUAGUUUCCAGUACUUUUUGUUGUUGUUGUUUUAGAGAGACAGGGCCUUGCUCUUUUGCCCAUGCUGGUCUCAAACUCCUGAGCUCAAGCAGUCCUCUGCCUCAGCAUCCCAAGUAGCUGGGACUACAGGCCUAAUACUUUUUGUGCCUGCUCCUCUCUUCCUGUUUCUACCCCAUCAUAUCUGCUCAGAUCUUCUUAUCAACUACUGCAGCAACCUGCUAAAAUGUCUCUCAAUCUUCUGGAUAAGUCAAUCAACUGCUAAAUGAAUCUUCCCUAAAUUUUACUUUUAUUGAGUUCUUCUGCUCAGAAACCUAUUUUUACUUCUUUCUAGUCCUCAGCAUGGUAUUUCUUUCUUCUAUGUUAAUUGACAGUCUGUCCUUAAAUAUGACUGUCUAUUCCUGCUCUUCCUUCCCUCAAACCCAAACUCACCCUUCUCAUCUCUCCUCUUCCCCAAACUGUUCUUCAUCUACCGUGCAGCCCAGUACACACGGGUAGUCCCAGUUCUUCCUUUGGAACUCUAGAGCAUAAGUAAUUCUCACUCUCUUGGUUUUACCGUCCUGAUACUGAUAUUGUUGGCUAACUAGUCAUUAUUUAUUUGUCAUAUGACCUUACCAGAUUUUUAGUACAUCAGAUUUGAUGAAUAUGUCUAGUACAAUGCUUCAAAUGUUGUAAGUACUCAUUAAAUGUGUUAUUGACUAAUUGAUAUGACUUUUUAGUUGACAAUUCUCUCCAGUUUUUAUGCAAUUCCUUAUGGUAAAUGAAGUGCAUUAACUUUUACAGGCCUCUGGAAUAAUCAUGAGUGCUGCACUGAUGCAAAAUAGUAAAUAUCAAUGGAUAGAAUUAUAUUUUUAAAUUUAAAUUUUGAAGCAGCAAUGACGUAAUAGAUAUGAGGGCUAUCUCCAUGUUUAUAUUUGUCCAUUCUUCAUGGAUAUCAUUGUAAGUCUGGUAGCAGAAUGGACUCAGCGCUCCUUGAGAGCUAGAAAUUAGAUUAGUCUUAAUAUGAAUAAUUUAUUAUUGCAUUCGGCCUCCUUCACUUGCAAGCUGGUUAACAUUGAGCCAGCCUCUAAACAACUCUCAGCUUCAAUUUCCCCAACUGUAAAAACAGGGAUGCUUAUUUCUACCUGCCUCAGUGUUCAGAAUUGGAUGUUUUUGUAGCUUCAAGAAAAAGAGUGGACUAACUGGAGUGGAGUUUAUAUAUAAUAAAAUGUAAAGCAGUCAACAGUGGCAAGUGCUAUAAGAGCUGUGUAGAUGAAGACAAACAAGUGCCUAUUAGCUCAUUUAAUGUUGGUCAUGGGUGAACUUCAAGCGUCAAUAAUUCAUUCACUGAACAAAUAUUUAUUGGGCUCCUACUUUUUGUCAAGCACUUGCACAACAAAUACACAGGAAAAGCCCCAACCCUCUUAGAGCUUACAUAUUGGGGAGAGAAAAAUGUUUCAUUAGAGUGAUAUGGAUUGCAGUGAGUUGAGAAGGACUUUGGAGAUGAGGAAGAGGGUAACAUAGAUUAUUCUUUCAAGAAAUGUGGAGGUAAAGAAGAGAACAGUAGGAGAGAAAAGCUCAAGUGAAGUAUGAGAUUGCUUGUUUUAUGGACCUAGAGACUGGGGCCACUUAUCAGUUGAGAAAAAGAGUCAGUGGCAGGAGAGAUGAAAAUGGUACAAGGACAAGAUGGAAAGAGGCCCUCUGGGGACGGAAAGAGGAAUAUGCAAUCAAUGGUUCAUGUGGAAGAGGUGAUAUCAUAGGAAAGAAGUAGAGAUGCCAUCUUCUUUGAUACUGGAUGAGAAGAGGUGCAGAGACUUAGACACAUGAUACCACGUCAAACUGAUUUCAAUCUGAUGCGGAUUACAUACAGGUUUCAAGAAAAAUAUAAACACGUGAAAGAAGAUCUUGCCCAUUUGCAUUUUGAGAAACUUGAAAGAUUUCAAAAACUCAAGGAAGAGCAAAGAUGUUUUGAUAUUGAAAAGCAAUACUUAAACAGAAGACGACAAAAUGAAAUAAUGGCCAAAAUCCAAGCAGCUAUUAUACAGAUUCCUAAACCUGCAUCAAAUCGUACUUUGAAAGCACUCGAGGCCCAAAAAAUGAUGAAAAAGAAAAAAGAGGCAGAAGAUGUGGCUGAUGAAAUUAAGAAGUUCGAAGCAUUAAUAAAAAAGGAUCUCCAAGCAAAAGAAAGUGCAUCCAAGACUUCUUUAGAUACAGCAGGCCAGACAACCACCGAUUUGUUAAAUACUUACUCAGAUGACGAGUACAUUAAAAAAAUCCAGAAGCGCCUUGAAGAAGAUGCUUUUGCACGAGAGCAAAGGGAGAAAAGACGGCGGAAAUUGUUAAUGGACCAGUUAAUAGCCCACGAAGCACAAGAGGAGGCUUAUCGGGAGGAACAGCUGAUUAACCGGCUGAUGCGGCAGUCCCAGCAGGAGCGCAGGAUUGCCGUGCAGCUCAUGCAUGUUCGGCAUGAAAAGGAAGUUUUAUGGCAAAACAGAAUUUUCAGAGAAAAACAACAUGAGGAAAGACGACUUAAAGAUUUCCAGGAUGCUCUUGAUCGAGAAGCGGCUUUGGCAAAACAAGCCAAGAUUGACUUUGAAGAACAAUUCCUUAAAGAAAAGAGAUUUCAUGAUCAGAUUGCUGUGGAAAGAGCUCAAGCUCGUUAUGAAAAGCAUUAUUCAGUAUGUGCAGAAAUUUUGGAUCAAAUAGUUGAUUUGUCCACUAAAGUGGCAGACUAUCGAAUGUUGACAAAUAAUCUGAUUCCGUAUAAGUUGAUGCAUGAUUGGAAGGAACUAUUUUUUAAUGCAAAACCCAUAUAUGAACAAGCCUCUGUUAAGACACUACCUGCUAACCCCUCAAGAGAACAACUUACAGAACUGGAGAAAAGGGACUUGCUAGAUACCAAUGAUUAUGAAGAAUAUAAGAACAUGGUUGGAGAGUGGGCCUUACCAGAAGAAAUGGUUGACAAUUUACCACCCUCCAACAAUUGCAUACUGGGCCAUAUUCUUCACAGGCUAGCUGAAAAAUCUCUUCCUCCUCGAGCGGAAUCAACAACACCUGAAUUACCUUCAUUUGCUGUUAAAGGAUGCUUAUUGGGGAAAACAUUAAGUGGAAAAACUACCAUUUUAAGGUCUCUACAAAAAGACUUUCCUAUACAGAUACUUUCUAUUGACACUCUUGUCCAAGAAGCUAUCCAAGCAUUUCAUGACAAUGAAAAAGUCAGUGAGGUUCUACCAAUUCAGAAAAAUGAUGAAGAAGAUGCUCUACCAGUUCUGCAAGAGGAGAUUAAAGAAAGCCAGGAUCCACAACAUGUAUUUUCAGCUGGUCCAGUUUCAGAUGAAGUAUUACCAGAAACAGAAGGUGAAACAAUGCUUAGUGCUAAUGCUGAUAAAACACCAAAAGCUGAAGAAGUCAAAUCAAGUGAUAGUUUCUUAAAACUCACUACACGUGCUCAGCUUGGUGCAAAAUCAGAACAGUUGCUGAAGAAAGGAAAGAGCAUUCCUGAUGUGCUGCUUGUUGACAUCAUAGUAAAUGCUAUUAAUGAGAUACCUGUGAAUCAAGACUGUAUCCUAGAUGGUUUUCCAAUGACUUUAAACCAAGCACAGCUUCUGGAAGAAGCUCUUACAGGCUGCAAUAGAAACCUCACAGAAGUGGAAAGAAAAAAAGCACAAAAAUCCACAUUGGCUAUUGAUCCUGCGACUUCCAAAGAAAUACCUCUUCCCUCUCCUGCAUUUGAUUUUGUCAUAUUAUUAGAUGUUUCAGAUACUUCCUCAAUGAGUCGCAUGAAUGAUAUUAUAGCUGAAGAAUUGUCCUAUAAAACUGCUCACGAAGAUAUCAGUCAACGUGUAGCUGCUGAAAACCAAGAUAAGGAUGGAGACCAAAAUUUAAGAGACCAGAUACAACAUAGAAUUAUAGGCUUCUUGGACAACUGGCCUUUAUUGGAGCAAUGGUUUUCAGAGCCAGAAAAUAUUUUGAUAAAAAUCAAUGCUGAAAUAGAUAAGGAAUCUUUAUGUGAAAAAGUAAAAGAAAUUCUUACGACUGAAAUAGCAAAAAAAAAGAAUAAAGUUGAGAAGAAAUUAGAAGAAAAGGAAGCUGAGAAAAAAGCAGCAGCUUCCCUGGCUGAGCUUCCACUUCCUACACCUCCUCCUGCUCCUCCUCCUGAACCAGAAAAAGAGAAGGAAAUUCAUCAAAGCCAUGUGGCUUCAAAAACUCCUACUGCAAAAGGAAAACCUCAAUCAGAAGCCCCGCAUGGUAAGCAAGAAUCUCUUCAGGAAGGAAAAGGGAAGAAAGGUGAGACCGCACUCAAAAGAAAAGGUUCUCCUAAAGGAAAAUCAUCAGGAGGAAAAGUACCAGUAAAGAAAUCACCUGCUGACUCUACAGAUACAUCACCUGUUGCAAUAGUGCCACAGCCACCUAAGCCAGGAUCAGAAGAAUGGGUCUAUGUGAAUGAACCAGUUCCUGAGGAAAUGCCUUUGUUUUUAGUACCUUACUGGGAACUAAUAGAAAAUUCCUAUAUAAACACCAUCAAAACAGUACUCAGGCAUCUGAGGGAAGACCAGCAUACUGUGCUUGCUUACUUAUAUGAGAUUAGAACAAGUUUCCAGGAGUUUCUAAAGCGUCCGGAUCACAAGCAAGAUUUUGUAGCUCAAUGGCAGGCUGAUUUCAACUCCCUUCCUGAUGACCUGUGGGAUGAUGAGGAAACAAAGGCUGAACUACAUCAACGAGUGAAUGAUCUGCGAGACCGCCUGUGGGACAUUUGUGAUGCCCGGAAGGAAGAGGCGGAGCAGGAGCGGCUUGACAUCAUUAAUGAGAGCUGGUUACAGGACACUCUUGGAAUGACAAUGAACCAUUUCUUUUCCCUGAUGCAGGCAGAGCUGAACCGUUUCCAAGAUACAAAGAGACUCCUUCAAGAUUAUUACUGGGGAAUGGAAAGUAAAAUCCCAGUAGAGGACAACAAGAGAUUUACUCGAAUCCCUUUGGUCCAACUGGAUAGUAAAGACAAUUCUGAAAGCCAGCUUAGAAUUCCUCUAGUUCCUCGAAUAUCCAUUUCUCUGGAAACAGUUACACCCAAACCAAAAACAAAAUCAGUACUGAAGGGCAAGAUGGAUAACUCCCUAGAAAACGUUGAGUCCAACUUUGAGGCCGAUGAAAAGUUGGUCAUGGACACCUGGCAGCAGGCUUCUUUAGCAGUAUCUCACAUGGUGGCUGCUGAAAUUCAUCAGAGGCUUAUGGAAGAAGAAAAAGAAAACCAGCCAGCAGACCCCAAAGAAAAAUCUCCUCAGAUGGGUGCAAAUAAAAAAGUCAAAAAGGAGCCACCCAAGAAAAAACAGGAAGACAAAAAACCCAAAGGUAAAUCACCACCUAUGGCAGAAGCAACUCCUGUCAUAGUAACAACAGAGGAAAUUGCUGAAAUCAAAAGGAAAAAUGAACUGAGGGUCAAAAUAAAAGAAGAACACCUUGCUGCCUUGCAAUUUGAAGAAAUAGCCACGCAAUUUCGACUUGAACUGAUAAAGACAAAAGCAUUGGCUCUUCUUGAAGAUUUAGUAACAAAGGUGGUUGAUGUAUAUAAACUCAUGGAAAAAUGGCUUGGUGAGAGGUAUUUGAAUGAAAUGGCCAGUACAGAAAAAUUAACUGACGUAGCUCGCUAUCACAUUGAAACAUCUACAAAAAUUCAGAAUGAACUUUAUUUAAGCCAAGAAGACUUCUUCAUUAAUGGCAAUAUAAAAGUCUUCCCAGAUCCUCCCCCAUCAAUACGUCCUCCACCUGUAGAAAAGGAAGAAGAUGGUACCCUGACCAUUGAACAGCUUGACAGUCUUCGAGAUCAGUUCUUAGAUAUGGCACCUAAAGGAGACAGGAAGUGGCUUCAUGGAUUACAGGCAGCCCUCCAGAACUUUCUCAAGGGAUAUCCUGCAAUUGUUCGGCAACUGCACUCAGCAGGCAGAGGCAAAAGUGACACCAGUCAAAAGAAACCCAAAGAACUUCUGGAGUCCCUUCUCCAAGCUGACAUUGUUAAAUUUGCCCACUUCUUGUUGGAUGUCAUGAAUGUCCUUAGCAUUCUGUCCUGUGUCAAUAAGAAUAGAAAUUCCUCAAUUGCUGACAUAUUUGCCACUUUAGAGUCAAUGCUGGAAAUGCUCCAAAUGUAUCAAACAAGACUAGGGCCAAAAGAACGCAUGGUGGAUUCAGCCACACACUUUCAUGGUAACUGCCUCAGAGGGAAAGAAAACAUUUCUGCUGUGAGAAACAUUGUUUUAACACAUCUUAUCAAGAGACUUCAAGGCUGUUUCAGAGAUGCCAGCCAAAAUGUGGUGAGGGCUACCGUGAUUGGAAGUUUUAAAUUGUGGCCCACAAAGAUAAAUCAAGAAUUUGGAGAAAAAGAGGUAUCCAUCCUGACUGCACAUUAUGAACCAGUAUUAGAAGCUGCCAAUGUGAAACUUAGUGAAGUGGAUACUGAAUGGAGCAUGUUGAAAUUAGAGAUUUAUGCCAGAUUUCAGAACAUUCGAAAAUUGACCUGGGAUUUUGUGAAUUCCAUUUACUUACACAAGUAUCCAAAUAUCCUGACACUAGUCGACCUAGUGUUGACCCUUCCUGCAAGUUCAGCUGAAGCAGAACAUGGCUUUAGUCAGAUGAAAUGGACCAAGUCACAUAUGCAUGCAAAAAUCAAGGCUGAAAGCAUAAUAGGAAAUAAAGCAUUUACUGACAUUCUGAUCGAUUUGGUGACCCUGAACCUUGGCACAAACAACUUUCCUAGUAAUUGGAUGCACCUUACCCAACCUGAAUUACAGGAAUUAACAUCUUUAUUAACAGUCAACUCCGAGUUCGUGGACUGGCGGAAGUUCCUGUUAGUAACCUCAAUGCCUUGGCCCAUUCCCUUGGAGGAGGAGCUCCUUGAGACCCUUCAGAAGUUCAAGGCUGUGGAUAAGGAGCAGUUGGGCACCAUCACUUUUGAGCAGUAUAUGCAGGCUGGUCUGUGGUUUACAGGAGAUGAAGAUAUAAAAAUUCCAGAAAAUCCUCUUGAACCCCUUCCAUUUAAUAGGCAGGAGCAUCUUAUAGAGUUUUUCUUUAGGCUAUUUGCUGACUAUGAGAAGGAUCCACCCCAGCUUGACUACACACAGAUGCUGCUUUACUUUGCUUGCCACCCAGACACCGUGGAAGGAGUCUACAGGGCCCUCAGUGUGGCUGUUGGAACUCAUGUCUUCCAACAAGUCAAAGCUUCCAUUCCAAGUGCAGAAAAGACCUCCUCAACUGAUGCAGGUCCAGCUGAGGAAUUUCCUGAACCUGAGGAAAAUGCUGCAAGAGAAGAAAGGAAAUUAAAAGACGACACGGAGAAAAGGGAACAGAAGGAUGAAGAAAUCCCUGAAAAUGCAAACAAUGAAAAGAUGUCCAUGGAAACACUACUCAAAGUGUUCAAAGGGGGAAGUGAAGCACAGGACUCCAAUAGAUUUGCCAGCCACCUAAAGAUAGAGAACAUUUAUGCAGAGGGCUUCAUAAAAACAUUUCAAGACCUAGGUGCCAAGAACCUGGAGCCAAUUGAAGUCGCUGUUCUCUUGAAGCAUCCUUUUAUUCAAGACCUGAUUUCAAAUUAUUCAGACUAUAAGUUUCCUGUACACAUCAUCUAUGUAGUGGAAAUGAUAGUGUGUGCAAAAGGUUGGGCACCACUUCCAUCAGGAAAACAGUGUGCAAGAUGGAGAAACUAAGGACAAACCCCAGAGAAACUGGACAAACCCAGCAGAAGAAAGGAAGAACUGCAACUCAGAAAUCACAUAACCACCAAGCAGGUCUGGACCACACAUGCUAAAUGUGCAUCCACUAUGGCGAGUCCCAGGCCUUUAACAGCAGGGACUAAGGAGGGCAGAGGCUGACACCAACCCCCUUUCAUACUGUAGCACUACAUCCCUCUCAGAUACCAGUUUAACACGAAGUCUCCCUGUUUGACUCCUGUGAGUUGUGUAUUGAACUACAAAGUGUUUGCUGAGUUGAAAAUAAAAGCGCUUUCACUUUGAUAGAA